GUGGCAGUUAGGGGACCUGGCCUGCUGAAUGGGUUGGGGCCUUCUCUUGGAUCAAGAGUCUCUUAUUUGAUCGAGGUCUGUUAUUAGACUUCCUCAUUCUUUCUCAGACCUCAGGCUGCAUGGUGGCAGCUGAUGAAAAUAUCCAAAAGAUGAGAAGAGACAAUUGAGUCUGGUGAGGGAAAGGGGAGACAGAGGGUGAAGUGGUGCUCAAGAUGGAUGCAGAGUACUCUGGGAAUGAGUUCCCCAGGUCAGAAGGAGAAAGAGACCAACAUCAGAGACCUGGAAAGGAAAGGAAGAGUGGGGAGGCAGGAUGGGGCACAGGUGAGCUGGGACAAGAUGGGAGACUGCUGUCCUCCACCCUCUCCCUCAGUAGUAACAGGUCCUUGGGCCAGCGCCAGAACUCUCCGCUGCCCUUUCAAUGGAGAAUCACACACAGCUUCCGCUGGAUGGCCCAGGUGUUGGCCUCUGAGCUCAGCCUGGUUGCCUUUAUCCUACUAUUGGUCGUGGCCUUCUCCAAGAAAUGGCUGGACCUCUCUAGGAGCCUCUUCUACCAGCGCUGGCCCGUGGAUGUCAGCAACAGAAUCCACACAUCAGCCCACGUUAUGUCCAUGGGGCUCCUGCACUUUUACAAAUCCAGGAGCUGUUCUGACUUAGAGAAUGGGAAAGUCACCUUCAUCUUCUCCACCCUCAUGCUAUUCCCCAUUAACAUCUGGAUCUUCGAGUUGGAAAGGAAUGUAUCCAUCCCCAUAGGCUGGAGCUAUUUCAUUGGUUGGCUGGUGCUUAUCCUAUACUUCACCUGCGCGAUCCUUUGCUACUUCAACCAUAAAAGUUUCUGGAGUCUGAUUCUGAGCCACCCCAGUGGUGCCGUGUCCUGCAGCAGCAGUUUCGGCUCAGUAGAAGAAUCUCCAAGGGCACAGACGAUCACAGACACCCCCAUCACCCAGGAGGGAGUCCUGGAUCCUGAGCAGAAGGAUACACAUGUGUAAUCUUUUCUGAACUCCUGGCACCAAGUUCUGUCCAUUCAUCUGACCCCAUCUCCUCAUCCUCCCCCAGCCCUUGAAUAGGUUGGUCCUCAUCAUUGCAAGGAAUGAGAAAGGGAGGAUUUUGCACUCCUCUGCUUUCUCCCUGCCUUGAUUGAGCUUGAGUGAUGUGGAAUAAAUUGUCCGUCUCUUCUUUCUCA